AGAACUAAGGCUGUGGGUAAGGCGACAUUUCCUGCCCCCGGGGCCAGGGUGAGAGGAGAGAUGAUGAGUUGCUGAGUGUGCACACCUUUCCGGAACACAUACACACACCCUGCUCUGGGAUCCCUUGUGAGGCUGCCCUCAUGGAGUUCCCCCUGGCCCAGAUAUGUCCCCAAGCCCUCUUUGUGCUCACAGGGAGUCACGAAGCCCCCAUCCCAACCUUCAGCACCUUCCAGAUCACAGACAUGACCCGCAGGAGCUGCCAGAACCUGGGCUACACUGCGGCAUCUCCCCAGGCCCCGGAGGCUGCCUCCAACACAGGGAAUGCUGAGAGGGCAGAGGAGGUGCCUGGAGAAGGAAGCCUGUUCCUGCAGGCCGAGACCCGGGCUUGGUUCCAGAAGACCCAGGCCCACUGGCUCCUGCAGCACGGGGCAGCCCCUGCCUGGUUCCAUGGCUUCAUCACCCGGAGGGUUCGGCCCCCUCUCUCCGUCACCCACAGGGAGGCAGAGAGGCUGCUGGAGCCCAAGCCUCAGGGGUGCUACUUGGUGCGGUUCAGCGAGAGCGCGGUGACCUUCGUGCUGACUUACAGGAGCCGGACUUGCUGCCGCCACUUCCUGCUGGCCCAGCUCAGGGACGGGCGCCACGUGGUGCUGGGCGAGGACAGCGCCCACGCGCGGCUGCAGGACCUGCUGCUGCACUACACCGCGCACCCGCUCAGCCCCUACGGGGAGACGCUCACCGAGCCCCUCGCCCGACAGACUCCUGAGCCUGCAGGACUUUCCCUGAGGACCGAAGAAUCAAACUUUGGAAGCAAAAGCCAGGACCCAAACCCCCAGUACAGCCCAAUCAUCAAACAGGGGCAAGCCCCAGUCCCGAUGCAGAAAGAGGGGGCCGGGGAGAAGGAGCCCUCCCAGCUGCUCAGGCCCAAGCCUCCCAUCCCCGCCAAACCUCAGCUGCCCCCAGAAGUCUACACAAUCCCUGUUCCACGACACCGCCCGGCCCCACGCCCCAAGCCCUCCAAUCCUAUCUACAAUGAGCCUGAUGAACCCAUAGCUUUCUAUGCCAUGGGCCGGGGCAGCCCUGGGGAAGCCCCCAGCAACAUCUAUGUGGAAGUGGAAGAUGAGGGCCUACCCGCCACCCUUGGGCACCCUGUCCUACGGAAGAGCUGGUCCAGGCCUGUCCCAGGAGGCCAGGUAAAUGGGUAUGCAGGGAAAGGUAGGUGCAAGAAGGUCUCCCUGCAGGUAGAUGGGGGAAGGUGAAGAAGGUGUUCAGAGUGGAUGCCUGGGGCAGGGUAAGGGGCAGAGGUGUGAGGUGAUGUGGGAAGAACAGAAUGAUCCAGGCACCAGCCUCCCUUCUCCAGGCCCAGAGGCUGCCCCCUCUUCUCCCCAGAGUCGCUCAGACCUCAUCUUUGUCAAGCCCCCAUGCCCUCCUAUCUCACACAGAAAACAGAGGCCCCCAGGCAGGGUGCCCCUCCACCUCCCACAUCGAGGCUUUUUUGAUCUGCGUCCAUCUUGUCCUGCAGGCCCUCUUCAGACGCACCUGGGGCUGACCCCACCCCGUGCCUCUCUGGCUCUCUCCCUUGGCCUUCACGGCCCUGCUGUCCUGGAGAAAAAGAGCACUUGGGUUCCCUUAUGUCAUCUCAGUGAGCUCAGGGGAGGGGGACCCUGCUCUCCCAGCCUGCUUCUGUGUACUCCCUGUCUCCCUCUUCCUUCUCCCCAGCCCUAAGUCUUCUUGCCUACCCUUCAAGUCAGUACCUCAUGCCAUGGGUUAGCCCCAGCAGCCAUCCCACCCUCUCCCUCGGCCUCUGCGGCCCUCCCAAAGCCCUUCCCCAGCCUCCCUCCUCAGACCCUUCCCCAUCCUCCCUCCUUGCUGGUGCCCCAGGCUCCCUGCUCAGCCUGAGCCUGCUCGCGCUCACCCACACCCCUGCCAACGUCUGCUGUCCUAGAGCUAACGUCACCUGUCCAUAUCUCCGUCCAAACUUUUUUCCAAGCUUCUGGUCAGUUCCCCCCAGCAUCCCUGAGCCCCUCAAACUCAACACGGCCAACAGCGCUCUCACCCUUGCCCUCCAAACAGCUCGGUCCCAUGUUCACUGUCCUGAUUGCUAACUCUCCAGCUACCCAGCUAGCCAAGCCAGAAUCCCAGGGCUCCCUCAGCACAGCUCCCUCUUUACUCCCCCAGUAAGCCACUCAUUCCUGCUGGAUCUCUUCCUAAGUAUAUUUUUCCUUCCCCCAGCUCCAGCCCCCAUCAUUGGGGUCUGGCUUUGUCACCCAGGCUGGAGUGCAGUGGCACAAUCAUAGCUCACUGCAAACUUGAACUCCUGGGUGCAAGUGAUCCUCCCACCUCAGCUGAGAUUACAGGCUCGAGCCACCUCACCUGGCUCCCAAGAGCUUCUUAACUGGUUUCCUAACCACCAUUCUUGCCACUUCUGAUCCACUCUGCACCAAAGAGCCAGAAUGGUCUUGCUGAAGCAGCUGCCUGGCCCAUGAAGCACUCUAGACUUGGGUUGGGUGGGGGGUCUCACCUCCUUAGCCUUACCACCAGCCACUCCCAUUCUCCUAGAAUGAUUCACAUUUCUCUAAACUCACCAAGUGGUUUCAAGCCUCCUGGGGUUUGCACCCGCCAGUAUCUCUGCCUAUAGCAACUUCCUGCAACCUCAUCCUCCCGCUGCCUGGCAACUUUCUAAUCAUCCUUCAAGACCAGCUUUCCCUUCUCAGAGGCCACCCCCUGUGCCUUACACACACCUGCCAUGCCACUGAUCACCUGAGACAUCCAUCUCCUCCCAUCUCCUUCUCUCUGUCCCUUCCCUAGUUUAGAGUGUGAGUUCCCUGAAGGGAGGGGCUGGGACUUACCCAUCUGUUUCCAAAGCACCCAGCCCAGUGCCUGGCACAGAGCAGGUGCUCAGGAGAUGUUUGUUGAAUUAAUGAAUGAGAGGAGUUUAGAUACCCUCUCUGGAAGCCAAAGUCUGUUCAGAUCAGAUGUCUUGAGACUGCAAGUACACCUAGGAGGCAGAGGGUAGAGGGUGUGACCUAGAACUGUCCUUCUCUCUGCAGAAUACAGGUGGCUCCCAGCUGCAUUCUGAGAACUCUGUGAUUGGGCAAGGCCCUCCCCUGCCCCACCAGCCCCCACCCGCCUGGAGACACACCCUCCCCCACAAUCUUUCUAGACAGGUGCUUCAGGACAGAGGACAGGCAUGGCUUCCCCUUGGGCCUCCUCAGUAGGCGGUAAGUCUGAGCUUGGUGAGGAUAACUUGGAGCAUCAGGUCCAGAGACCUUCACACACACCUGGCACACUUCUCAAGAAAUGUGGAUGGAAUAAACCAUAGGUGUUCAAAGCUGGAAAGGAGCUCAGCCAUCAUCUAUUGCAAGGAUGGCAAAGAGGUGUCAUCUUGCAUGCCAACUCCAAUCCAUUGGUCGUGGCUGCCUAGAGUGCUGCAUUGGAAAGGAUGUUAAGGUCAUAUCUGAACUCAGCAGAAAAAAAGCACAUGAUUGAUUAGUGAUGUCUGCCACGGGUAAGAGCGGGAGGAUGAGCAGCAUUACAUUUGUCCUUAGUGAUCAAAUUCAGCUCCCUCACUAUGCGGAGAAGAAAACAUAGCCUGAGAGGGACAGUGACUUGGCCAAGGUCAAGGACUAGAACCAGGCUUCCUGAUUCCCUGUUUAGUGCUUUGUUCCUUACCACACAUCCACAAACUCAAGUCCAUAGGAAACAUCAGAGAUUUCCUCAAACAGGAAGUCUGGCCACUUUCCAGAGUUCUACUGCAUGGAGGCCUGGGUGCUUCAUUGGUCCCCUCCUGUGGAUCCUGGCUUAACUCUGUCCCCCUGACAGGUCUGGCCUGACCCCCAACAAAGAAGCCUGGAGGUCAGAGAAGCAAAUGCGGAGCCUGCUCCCUCCUAAGAAGAUCCCAAGAAUCCAAUGGCUCAGUCCUUGGUGAUCUAAGACAGCAAAGAAGUGUGCAAGGAGGGCCCUGUUAGCUCCCACUGUCCUGGUUUCUCCUCCUGGAGUCUAAUUUCCUUGGCCCUCUGAGCCUUUUGAGUCUGGGCCCUGGUCCAAUGCUGCUGUUGUCUGAGGAAUGGUUUGGUGAGAACAGAUGUUAGAACUUGUUUGUUGAUUCUUGUCUGGCUAAUAAAUCAUCACCAACUGCCUUCUCCUACAGGGA